AAGUUACUGUGAGGCGGCGGCUAAGAAGGCGGCUCUGGUGGCGGCGGUGGAGGCUGAGGCGGCGGCCGAGGCGGCGACGGAGGAAACAGAAGAUGGCAGAUUUUUUGAAAGGACUGCCUGUCUACAACAAAAGCAAUUUUAGUCGAUUUCACGCGGACUCCGUGUGCAAAGCCUCGAACCGACGGCCCUCAGUCUACCUGCCUACCCGCGAGUACCCGUCUGAACAGAUCAUCGUGACAGAAAAGACAAACAUCCUCCUGCGCUACCUGCAUCAGCAAUGGGACAAAAAGAACGCUGCCAAGAAGAGAGACCAGGAGCAAGUGGAGCUGGAAGGCGAGAGCUCCGCACCUCCCCGCAAGGUGGCGCGGACCGACAGCCCAGACAUGCACGAGGACACUUAAGACUCUCAACUCCACAGGCGCCUCCUGCCAGGUCUGCUCCUCGGUCGCCCACCCGCCUGCCCGCCAUGUGUAAGCACCCCGCCCGCCCGCCUCCCUGCCGGCCCAUCCACACCCUGCGUCCACACCACUUCCAACCUCAUAGGAGCCGAUGUAUUUAUUUUCCUUGAGUUUUUAUUUAUGCUGUAACCUGUAUCAAGCGUUGGUUAAAGGGGACAUCAGACCCAGUAGUGUGAUGUUGGUAGAUGCUUUUUAAAAAAAACAACAUUGUCCCCCCGACCCCCGCCUUCCAUCGGGCCAGUUCCCCGAUUCCUGCCCCCAGUUCUCCAGAGAACCAGAGUGUGUCUGUGAGAGUCUCUAGCGGGGGCUUUACUGUGGCCGGGCGACAGGGGCGGGCCCGGGGUGGCCUGACCUACCAGGACAGCCGAGUGGCCUUCUCCCCCCCAACACCGGUCCAGGCCAUUGAGACUCGGUCUUGUCCCACGCUUCGCCCGGAACUUUCCCAUGCCCAGGCCUCACUCAGCGUGCACGCACGUUGGGGAGAAGUCGGCCCUUGGGAUCUUUCUCUUGAGUCAUUUUAUUUUUAUCAUGGACUAGUGCGUGCUCCGUGUCCACCCCAAUAAAAGGGUCUUUCCUACUUGACCUCGCGUCUUUGCUCCACACACCUUGGCUGCAGAGGACGGAGCCCCUGGGAGUCAUCCCUGUUGUCACCAAGAGGAGUGAGAAGGGCCCCCCACGCCAGGGGCCCCAGGACCGGCUGGAUUCUCUCGUGGGCUUGCUGAGGCCACCAUGUUCAAGGCCAAGACCUGCCUGGACCAUCCCCUCUGCCUCUCCUGUCAAGGUGACCCCAAGGACAGGUCAUUCCUGAGAGACGGUCCAUGGUGCCAAGGAUGGAGCGGGGUCAGCCCCCUGCCUGGGAUACCGCCAAGCAGGGCAGCGCACCUGUCAGACACCGCAGAGAUGGCCGGCCUCAUCCGGGGGCCUGGGGUCUCUGGCCUCUGCUGCUCCCCUGAGGCAUGGUGACAGUACAGACGGCAUCUGGCCGGUCUUGCUGUCCUAGGUGGUGGCCUCACCCUUGCUGGGUCAUAGAGGAGCUGUACAGAAGGUUGGCACCUGGCAGUUGGCAUGUGCCAUGGCCGCUCAUGGGGACCCCUCUUCCGCCAGCUGGGCUGGGUUUGGGGCUGAGCUUGGGUAUGUAGGGGUGUUCGGGCUCUGGGCAGAAGGUUUGUGGCCCUGACCACUGAGCCUGGGGCUGGGGGAACACCGCUUCUCCCCUUAUUGCCCCCACUGGUGGUGGUGGGGAUCUCAGUUUUCUUUUGUUUUGUUUUGUUUGUUUGUUUGAGUUGGGGUCUUGUACUCUUUCCCAGGCUGGAGUGCAGUGGCGUAAUCACAGCUCACUGCAGCCUCGACCUCAAGCCUUCCUCCCACCUCAGCCUUCCAAGCCGCUGGGACCACAGGCACCCACCACCAUGCCUGGCUAAUUUUUUUUUUUUUUUGAGAUGGAGUCUCGCUGUGUCUCCCAGGCUGGAGUGCAGUGGCAAGAUCUCAGCUCACUACAACCUCUGCCUCCCAGGUUCAAGUGAUUCUCCUACCUCAGCCUCCUGAGUAGCUGGGAUUACACGCGUGCGCCCCUACACCCAGCUAAUUUUUCUAUUUUUAGUGGAGACGGCGUUUUGUCAUGUUGGCCAGGCUGGUCUCGAACUCCUGACCUCAGGUGCUUCGCCUGCCUCGGCCUCCCAAAGUGCUGUGACCGCACCUGGCUGCCUGGCUAAUAUUUUAAAAAUUUUUUGUAGAGACAGGGUUUCACCAUGUUGCCCAGGCUGGUCUCAAACUCCUGGGCUCAAGUCAUCCACCUUCCUCAGCCUCCCAAAGUGCUGGGGUUACAGACGUGAACCACCGUGCCUGGCAGAGGUCUCUGUUUUGAGAGCUGAGUCUGAGGGCGUUGGGAUGGUGUAGGGUUGGGCCACAGAGCUAGCAGACACUCCGGGCUAUGGAGGGUCCGCCUGCCCCAGAUUCCACUGUGGAGGGCCCUGCCUGUGUCAGACCCUCGGGCCUAGGCGGCCCAUCUCUCCCAAGGACGGAGAGUGCCAGGGUGGGCUCCCGUCCUACACAAGGAGUGGCUGACCAGGCCCAGGCACAGCACAGCCACCCUGCUGUACCUCCCAGCUCCCGGCAGUGUCUACACCACAGUGAUGGUGCUACAGGGGCCAUGUGGUCACAGGACAGGUGGUCAGGAAAUGCACACUUGACUGCGGUCGAUGGUGCCGGGUCCGGCUGAAUGCCCUGGAGGCUCCCAGGCCAGCUGGGGAGUCCCAGUCCCCAGGGUUGGUGUGACCUGGGCAGGCCUGCGGUGUCCAUCUGUGAAUGACUGAGAUGGUGGGACUUCAGCUUCCAAGGCCAGGGGCCAGAGUGGGAGCAGGGGGCACUCCCGCCUUUCCCCUCGGCCUGUCUAGACCUCUCUGGCUCCCAGUUUCUGCUUUGAGUGGCUGGGGGCUGUCUCCUGCCUGUGCUGUCUGCCCGUCGCUCUGCAGGGCUGCUGGGCGGGCACCUCCUUCCCCUCCCCUACCUCAGCUCCCUCCUUUGGGGUCUGAGGGCUGUGCCCCAGCUUGCCUCCCUGUGGCCUCCCCCUAGAACCCCUGGGUCUGUCGGGACAUGCCCCACCUGGCACACACACCCUGUGUAGCUCCCACUGCCUGUGGGAGGACGCUGGGCCCCUGAGCCGGCCUCUGUCUACCCCUCCUGCCUUUGGGGUCCCCUUUACCCCACUGUUCCCCCAAACUGCCUUCCACCUUCUCCGCCUUUGCACAGGCUGUUCUCCUGCCUCCAGUGAACUCUGACUUCUCCACAGCCUCCCAAAGGGCCCCUUGCUCACACUGGCCCAGCCCUGCAGCAUGGCCAUGUUGGUCUCUGAGCCUUAAGCCUUUGGAUGUGGACACAUUUGUCCUCUUCCUGAAAAAUGUGAGGGUCUGAGAGGCCACGUUCCUGUUCCUGAGUCAUACGACAGAGUCCCAGUGACUUGGGUCUGAUGUCUGUCCCACAGUGGGACAUCCCUGCUGCAUCCCAAUGCCACCCCGUGUCCUGGGGACACCCAAAUGUGCCAUUCUCUCAGUAUCACAAGUCGGGGACUGCAGGAGGCUCAGGUGCCAGGUGCCUUCUGAUGUUCAUGCCACAAGCUCUUCCCACUGUCUCUGGCUCCCCAGACGAUGUUCCAGGAGGCGGGUGUGCCAGAAGGGGCCACGUCUUGCAAACCACCGCGCUGUCCUCUUUGAGAAGGAGUCUUACUCAGGACUGGGGCCUGUGCACACAUUGUCGCCUCUUUUCAGCACUUAGAGAUUCCUUCCUUUGUCUAGUGGCUGAAGCCAGGGCUGAAGUUGGCCUCCAAAUCUGGGCCGUCUCAGAGGCGGCGCAGCCUGGAGUUUUCCAUCUGUGGCCAAGACCCAGUUUUUGGGAGGAGGCCCUCAUGGGUCAAGCCAGCCUGUACCAGGAUGGGGGGAGGGGGUUCCCAACCUAGGCCCCAGCCACCCAGACUCCCCCACCCCCACUCCCUUUUCCACUGCUCUGACCUCGGGCACUGUUGAAAUAUAGUUUUUAUUGCAUUUCUGCCGUUUUACAAAAAUAUGACAAAAUAAAUUAAAAACAAAUAAA